AAUUGGCGGACUAGGAAGUGGAGCUUCUGUAUAUUUCUGUUUCUCAUUUCUUGGGGAGAGUACCGGCGGGAAGGUCUGUGCCUUGGGCCGUCGUGGGUCGGAAUUUGCAGCUGAGAGGAGAGGAGUCCGGUGCCGCCGUCGCCCCCCUCACCUAAAUACCCGGGCCCCUGGGGUUGCAGGCAGGGGCGGGUCUUUGGGGCCAGAUUUGAGGAGGGAGUCGGCUGCGGUUUCCUCCCUCGAAGCCAUUCCCCAAAAUGAGCAUUUCCCGCCCAUUUGCCCUACCUCCUCCCAGGGGCUCGUGACCCAUUUUUUUUUUUUUUUUUUGAGACCGGAGUCUUGCUCUUGUCGCCUCCUGACCCAUUCUUUUUAUUCUUCUCUACAGCAUCCAUUCAUAUAUUCAUUCAGUCAGCUAAUUUUUAAUCCAGCACAUACUAUUGCAAGCGCUGUUUUAGGCGUUGAGAAUACAACUGUGAACAAGACGACAAAAAUUCCUGCCCUCAUGGAGCCUAAGAGCCUAAAUUUUAGCGAAGGUAGAACCACCGUAAACAAUGUAUAUAUUAAUAAGUAACUUAUGCACCAUACUGGAAAAUUAUAAAGUGCUAUAGAGGAAAAGAAGAAUUCAUGUAAAGCAAGGUAAGGCCCAUCAGGAUUGGAAGGAGGGGAUAGGCUGCAAUUUUAAAUAAGGCACUCAGAGUAGACCUCCUUGGGAAGAUGACCUAUAAGAAAACACUUGAAGGAGGCAAGAUUAUUAGCCAUGGAGAUCGCUUAAGGUGAAGGGAGCAGCCAAUGGAAAGGCCCUAAGAUGAAAGAGAAGGAAGGUCGGUAUGGCUGAAGAUUGAGGGAGUGGGAGAAGAGUAGAAGGUGUUGAGAAUGACACAUCCUGUAGACUUGUAUGCCACUCUUAAGACUUCAGCUCUUAUUUUGGGUGAGCAGGAGAGGAAGUUAGAAGUCACGGGCACAUUCAGUAGGGCCUUGUAUACCUCGGUAAGGACUUCAGGUUUUAUUUUAAGUAUGAACCACUGGAGAGUUUUCAGCAGAGCGAUGAAAUGAUCCAACUCAAGUUGUAAACGGACUACUCAGACUGCCCUAUUAAGAAAGGAGGAAGGCAAGGAUUGAAGAAAGGAGACCAGUUAGAAGACUACCGCAGUAAUGGAAAGGAGGGGAGAUAGCAGGUGAUGGUGGCUCAGACAAGGGUGGUAGCCGUUGAGAUUGUAUUCUGGAUAUGUUCACAUUUUCAGUUUGACUUCGUGCCUCAGGUUCUCAGUGACUCCCUAUUUUUUCCUGUGGUCACAUUCCUCUUUUCCCUUCACCAAAUAUGCAGGGAAACAAGAUGUGAGAUCACAGCGGUUUAGUGUUGCUAAUGAACCCCAAAUCCAGGGCAGUGUUUGACACAUUAAGCCAAACAGUAGCGGCACUGUGGGUCAAGAAGGGCCCUUUGGCUGGCACCACCAAAACAUGUGUUCUCCAAAGGAGGCUGGCAUCAACUGGAGCCACUUCACAGCUUGUUUGAGAACUGGAUCUGACCAGUAGGAAGAAACCAGGACAGCAGUGGAAGACUGUUAAAGAAACCUGAGUAAAAAGAUGCAGGAGGUUGUGCUGUUGGAUGAGAGUUCAGGACCACCAAGCCAGCUGCUUUGGACCCGCCAGGAUACCCAGCUCCCUCAGGAAAGCGCUCUAUUACCUGCUCCAUAUCCUGCCUUCACUAAAGAUGGAAGCCAAGGAAACCUGCCGCAAGCAGAUAUCACACUAAUGAGCCAGGCCCAAGAUAGCAGGAGCAUAUUAUUUCAGGAGUCAGUGACAUUUGAGGAUGUAGCUGUGAACUUCACUAACAGGGAGUGGCAGUGUCUGACCUACGCUCAAAGGCAUCUCUAUAAGGAUGUGAUGUUGGAAAAUUAUGGGAACAUGGUAUCACUUGGAUUUCCAUUUCCUAAACCUCCUUUAAUCUCUCAUCUGGAGCGAGAAGUAGACCCCUGUGUGCAGGAUCCACAGGACAGGGAGUCCCUAAGCUGCUCCUACCCAGUGUCAGCUGACAAGAUGUGGCCUGAGAAUGAAAAGGCAAGUUCACAACAAGAGAUUUUUGAAAAUGGAGAAGCCUACUGGAUGAAAUUUAACAGUCUCCUAAAAGUUGAUUCCCGGGAUCCUAAGGUUAGAGAAGUUUGUGUUCAGGAUGUCAAAUUAGAGAAUCAAUGGGAAACAUCUAUAAGGGAGAAACUGAGAGAAGAGAAAGAAGGCUCUGAGGAAGUGACCUGCAAAAAAGGAAAGAACCAGAAAGUGCUUAGUAAAAACUUGAAUCCAAACUCAAAACAUAGUCAAUGUAAUAAAGUUCUUAUAGCACAGAAACUCCAUGAAUGUGCCAGGUGUGGCAAAAACUUCAGUUGGCACUCAGAUCUAAUUCUCCAUGAGCAAAUUCAUUCUGGUGAGAAACCCCAUGUGUGUAAUGAGUGUGGGAAAGCAUUCAAGACCAGAAAUCAGCUUUCUAUGCACCGGAUAAUCCACACAGGGGAGAAACCUUUUAAUUGCACCCAGUGUGGGAAGGCUUUCAACAGUAGAUCAGCUCUUUGCCGACAUAAAAAAACCCACAGUGGGGAGAAGCCUCACGAGUGCAGGGACUGUGGGAAGGCCUUCAAGACCAGGAACCGUCUCUGUAUGCAUCAGCUUAUCCACACCGGGGAGAAGCCUUACAAAUGUAACUGCUGUGGGAAGGCCUUCCAGUUUAAGCAUUCCCUUACCAUCCAUGGCAGAAUCCACACUGGGGAGAAGCCAUAUGAAUGUGAGGAGUGCGGGAAGGCCUUCAGUGGGAGUUCAGACCUCACCAAACACAUAAGAAUCCACACUGGGGAACGACCUUAUGAGUGCAGCAAGUGUGGAAGGGCCUUCAGUCGGAGCUCAGACCUAAGCAAACACAAACGAAUCCAUACUCGGGAGAAACACUAUGGGUGUCCCCAGUGUGGAAAAGACUUCAGCAUCAAGGCAGAACUCACCAAACACAGAAGGAUCCACACUGAAGAGAAACGUUACAGGUGUGAGGAGUGUGGGAAAGCCUUUCGUCAUAACUGUAAGCGCAGGGCUCAUGAACGAGAGCAUACAGGGGAGAAGCCCUAUCAAUGCAGGGAUUGUGGGAAAACCUUCCAAGAUAAGCACUGCCUUACCAUCCAUCAGAGAAUCCACACUGGAGAGAAACCUUACAAAUGUUUAGAGUGUGGGAAAGCUUUCAGUGGGAAGUCAAACUUGACCAAUCAUCGAAGAAUUCACACUGGAGAGAAGCCUCACAAAUGUGAGGUAUGUGGAAUGGCCUUCCAUCAUAGUUCAGUCCUGAGGCAGCACAAAAGAAUCCACACUGGUGAGAAGCCAUACACCUGCAGUGAGUGUGGCACGUCCUUCCGUCAGGGCUCAGCUCUGAUUGGACAUAAGCGAGUUCAUACUGGGGAGAAACCUUAUGAAUGUGAGGAAUGUGGAAAAGCUUUUAGAGUGAGCUCAAAUCUUACUGGACAUAAGAAAAGAAAACAUCAAGUAUGGAGUACCCAUGAACUUGAUGGGAGUAGGAAAUCCCUCUCUCCAGUGACUGUUUCUCAGACCUCAGUAGUCAGUAUUUUGACCAGUGCCUGAGUAUAACGAUUCUGGUGUUACUUUCUGUUUUUCCUACCUCUUAGGCUGGUCCUUCUGUCUCUUAUAUUAGUUAUUCCUGAUUUCCUGACCCUUAAUUGUGAGAUUCCCCAAAGACAUUGUCCUUUACCUUCUUAUUCACUAUUUUUUCAGUGAGCACAUUUACUUCCAAGAGUUUAUCAAUCACUUCCUAAUAUUAAUAAACACUUAUUAGUG